AUGGGGAAUAUAACCAGGAAAGGAAGCAGAGACCUGGUGGUUGACAGUGCCAAGUCCCUGGAAGAUGGCCCAUCUGCAGCACUUCACUCGAAACUCUAUGAAGCCAUCAUGAGAGAAGACUGCACUACGAUCGAGGUACUCCUGAGAAAUCACCCUGUCAACCAGCCCAUCACCAUUCUGCCCAACUCCGCCAGCAACAGAUUACUUCUGACCCAGCCGACAGAGUCUAUCAUCCCCAUCCAUCUGGCUGCCAAGUACCACAAGGCCCAGAGUCUGCUCUGCCUGUUACGGCACGGUGCUGACCCAGAAGUCAGGGACACGACAGGCCUCACCACACUCAACUUAAUGCUACUGCACUGGCCAGUCACUUCCACCACGUGGGCAAAACCAGGCAACAGAACGCACAGGAUCCUGACAGACAUUCAGAAUAGCAGCAUCACAUGUCUCCGCAUCUUGUGUGCGCACGGAGCUCAAGUGAACACUCAAGGGGAAAUCAGCAACAAACGUUCACCACUCCACCUGGCCAUAGCAUAUGGUUGCUAUCCAGUUCUCUCCAUUUUGACCCAAAAUGGUGCCGAUGUCAAUGCUAUUAAUGAAGCCAGCAUGACACCCCUUCACAUGGCCGCAAACAUGCUGAAUAAGGAGAUGAUGGAAACGCUCAUUGCCUAUGGAGCAAACGUCAACUGUGCUGUCUCUUCCACGGGGAACACGCCCCUGAAGCUUGCAGUGUGCACUGCAUCAAGCAAAGCAGGCCGACUCCUCGGGGCGGGGGUCAGCUGCAUCCGUCUGCUACUCACUCACGGAGCCAAAGUCAACGCCCAGGACUACAAGGGCCAAACAGCCAUCCAUGAGGCAUGCUUUGGAGGCAGAGAGGCAAUCAUCAAUCUCCUGCUUGAAUUUGAAGCAAAUGUUAACAUUUUAACAAGAAACGGGGAAUCUCCAAUUUAUAUGUACCUUCAGCGCAGUUGCAAUGUAAGAGAUACGGCACUUCUGGCCAGGCUACUUUAUCACACUUAUCCUCUGAGAAUGACCAAUAACCAAGGAAUUCUACCUGCAGGAAUCAUGCUACCAGAAUUCCGCCUCUUAAGGGACACCCUAAUAAAGCAAUCGCAAAAACCUUUAUCCCUACAGGGUAUCUGCAAAAGAAACAUCAGGAAUAUUUAUGGUGAGAAAUACAAACAGCACUUGAAGCAAUUCCUCCCAGUGACAAUAUGGAAUUCUGUCUACUGCUGUUAUGACUUGGCAUAUACCUCUUGAAAUAAGACCUCCCAGUUUCACAGCAGAGGGACUUUCAGCCACUCAAACUGCAUUUUCUGGCUAGACAUGUCCCAGAAAAUGCUUCACCUAUCACCUGUGACAUCCCAAAUGUACAAACUACUGAUUCUUGAACAUGUUCCAAAAUACAAAGUGAUUUGUCUAUUAA